CAAUGCUGCAUUCUGGGCAGCCAGGAGAGGAAACCUGGCGCUGCUGAAGCUGCUGUUGAACAGCGGCCGGGUGGACGUGGACUGCAGAGACAGCGUACGGUGGUUCGGUAGAUGCAUGCCCAGCAUGCACCAUUGCCCUCUGUGGGCACAGGAGCACCUCAGGAAUACAUUCCCCUUUACAAUGCUUAUUUACUUUUUCAUGUGUUUGCUUGCUUUAUCCUUUUUAAAACAUCCAAGGUACUGUGGUGAACUUAAAAACAUGCUGGGGGAAGUCAGAAAGAAAAGGAAACAAUGAAAUGCAUAAAACAGAAGGCAACCACAAUAGGGAAAGAGGCACUUCACUGGGAAUCAGAAUUGGCAGAUUACAAGAAGAAAAGCCUGUUUAGUGAAAGAAUUCAAGCCAACCACUUCCAUGAAAAGAUGGAGAUAAUUUAGAGCACAAGUGGGCUGCCAUGGAUGUGGGCGUUAUGUUUCUUCUACAAGGAUGAGAAAACAAAAAUUGAAGCCUCCCCCAGGAUUUUAUCCUUUCAUUACCUCUUGAAAACAUAAAUACACUAAUUGGCAAUUUAAAAAGGGAAACAAAAAUAGAUACUACUGCCCACUGGCAGAUACCACUUAGAGAGCUUUUCCAUCCCCAGCUAGAGGCAAUCGUUUUUCUGUCCUCAGCAAGACUUCUCAUCUCUGGGACCAAGAGGACCUCCAAUGAGGAAAGGGAGCGAGCAAUGAUGUUUUGAUUUUAGGAUUUGAAUAAAAAUGUUUCAAAGGAGCUUUGUUUUCCUGAAAACAGGGUGUGCCAUUUCCAGCUUUUAUUGUACAAAUUUGAAAUCUACCACAAGCCCAAAAGUGAAAUAGCAGUUUGCCCCAGUUGGCCCCGUGGGGGCAUCACAGUAGGAUAUCUUUGGUUUACGGGAUAUCUUUGGUUACACCUCCAGACCCACUCCACACCCUUCUCGCUCUUAGUCCCACAGUCUGAAUUGUAUGUACUGCUCCAGCAGACUCGCUUUCCUCUGGCCUCCAGUUGUGUUUGGCCCAUAGGAGCAUCUGCAGGAGUCAGAGGGUAGGAGGAGAGGGACAUCAGGGAGCCCACCGCCCUCCCUGUUUCUGUCUGGCAGCAGCGCCCCACUGUUCUCUGCAUCCUGGGAGCCGCUCCCUUCCCCCCUGGCACCUUCAGGCCUCAGCUGGUCAUGGACCCCCACUGUUCCUAGAUCCCAGUACUGUGCUGUUCUUUGUAGAUGCCCUACACCCAGGCCUCAGCUUAAUAGUCUCUUUAUUACACUUUCUUCCAAUUAUCCCAAUCUGAAUGUACCAUCUGUUCCUUGCCAGAACUCGGGCUGCUGUCAAGUCUUGGGCAUCUGUGAACUGGCCAUCUUGGUCUUAUUUGGGUUUUACGGGGCUGGUUCCUACAUCACAGUGGGAAAACUGUAGGGCAGAAACACCAGUUGUCACCGUGGCCAACACGGAGAAACCCGCCUCUACUAAAAAUACAAAAAUUAGCUGGGCGUGGUGGCAGGCGCCUGUAAUCCCAGCUACUCAGGAGGCUGAGGCAAGAGAAUCACUUGAACCUGGGAGGCGGGGGUUGCAGUGAGCUGAGAUCGUGCCAUCCCACUCCAGCCUGGGAGGCGAGACUUCGACUCAAAAAAAAAAAAUACCAUAGAGCACCACUAAGAAGCCAUUAGCUUUUUGUUACUUCGUUACUUCGUUACUUUACCGAUACUUUUUACAUAAAGCCAACAAGACUUUCACAAAACUAGCAUGGCCAUUGACAGAAGUCAACAAAAGCCAGAUGACAGCCUAACAUUGAAUUAUCGUAAUGUUAUUUUAAUAUCUAACACUUACUGAACGAAUAUCUACCAUUACUAUGUUAACCAUAUUGCCUGACUUAUCUCAUUCAGUAAUUUAAUCAGGUGGAUACUUUUAUUAUUCCCCCAUAUUUCAGAUGAAGAGAAUGAGACUUAAGGGUUACAUGAUGUGCCCAAGAUCAUACUGUCAGUGACUACUCAGCAAUACUGCCUUCCUACAAAAUCCCGUAGAUGAAAAUAACACGAAGCCUCCAAAAUUCACUUAAUUACCCUAUACCUAAUGAGCCUCCCCUGUGUGCAGAGUCACCUGUCUCUCUCAUCAUCCACUUCUGAGCAGCAGGUUGCUGAAUAUGCAGAGGUGGUAGCUAAGAUUACAAUUUCAAGUGCUUGAAAACAACUGUAAGUCAAACUGCAAAUGCCCACUUCAAUUAGAAGGGUCCAUAUCACAUGGUACACCUCAGGUCCUUGAAUCUUAAAGCUGGGACAGACUUUGGUGAUCAUCCCAUCCAACCGCUCAUUUUAAAAAUGAAAUAAAUGAGUCCAAGUAAUUGUAAGCAACUUGCCCAGGUUACACUGUUGGUCAGUGACAGCUACCUGGGUUUAGCCCCCACAGCUCCUGACUCUCAACUCUGUAGUCUCUCAUUUCACCUGGUGCCAUACAUCUUUACCUGAAUCAUUUUGAAGAUGAAGACUUUUAAAUAUGGAAAAUCAGAUGGUACCAUUUAAUUUUUCUUUUGCAUUAAUAGCAAUGUUUUGGCUCAGGAAUCAUUUAAUAGGAAUCAUAAAAUGAGAGCAAUAUAUCAUCGCUGCCUUAAAAUGCAGUAACUAUGGUUCAUUUGGACUGUGCUUCUGAAGGUAAUGGAAGGAAUUUUGCCCUUGGAUGUGUUCUGAGUGGAGCUGACAUCUCUGCAGCAUCUUCUCUAGGACCCUUCUCUCUGACAUAGCAGUGGCCUAACUCUUCAUCUGUCUCUCCUCCAUCCAGCAUGGCACCACACUCCUGAUGGUUGCUGCCUACGCUGGCCACAUAGACUGUGUGAGGGAACUGGUUCUGCAAGGAGCAGACAUCAAUCUCCAGAGAGAGUCAGGUACAACUGCCCUAUUCUUUGCCGCCCAGCAAGGCCAUAAUGAUGUCGUGAGAUUUCUCUUUGGAUUUGGAGCAUCCACUGAAUUUAGGACCAAAGACGGGGGCACCGCCCUGUUGGCUGCCAGUCAGUACGGGCACAUGCAGGUGGUGGAGACCUUGCUGAAGCACGGAGCAAACAUCCAUGACCAACUUUAUGAUGGAGCCACUGCCCUCUUCCUAGCUGCCCAAGGUGGUUACUUGGAUGUUAUUCGAUUACUGCUGGCUUCAGGAGCAAAAGUCAACCAGCCAAGGCAGGACGGGACAGCGCCCCUGUGGAUCGCGUCCCAGAUGGGCCACAGCGAGGUGGUGCGGGUGAUGCUGCUGCGCGGAGCCGACCGCGACGCUGCGCGGAACGAUGGCACAACAGCAUUAUUGAAAGCAGCCAACAAAGGGUAUAAUGAUGUCAUAAAAGAGUUGCUUAAAUUCUCACCCACUCUUGGUAUUUUGAAGAAUGGGACAUCAGCGCUCCAUGCAGCAGUGCUCAGUGGAAACAUUAAAACAGUUGCGCUGCUCCUAGAAGCAGGGGCAGACCCAUCCCUGAGAAACAAGGCCAAUGAACUUCCGGCAGAACUAACCAAAAAUGAACGUAUAUUGCGUCUCCUGAGAAGUAAAGAAGGUCCCAGAAAGAGCUAACUUAGCUCCAUAUUUGACAGAAAGAUAGAAAGCUUAACCACAUUGUCCAAAAAGAAAUUGCAUUUCAAGCAGUGUUGGAAAUUCUUUUAUGAAAAAAAAAGAUGCCCAGAAUGCCCAUCCUGUGGGUCCCUGACAAAGAAGAGCUACGCUCUGUGCACGAAGUCAAGAACCAAACAGCUCAGGGACCCUCUUGCCCCUUCACCAUGGACUUCUCAUGGUGUCCUGUAACUCAUCUCCCGGGGGGCCUGGCAUGUUCACAGAUUCCACAGAAACUCAUUUUCAACAAUGCUAACUUGGACCUGUCAGUUAAACUCUAAGGUGGACAGGGUUCUCAGUACUAAGCAAGGAGACAGAAUGCUUUGUUCCUUUAAAAGACUGAAAAGCUGACCUUCAAUGGAUUGAGGCACUUUUGCUUUUGUGUUAAAUGUAGAUGUGCUAAAAUAUAUAGAUCUAUCAUAUUUUACCUACAUAUGUAUGUCAUUCCAGUAUAAAACAUUCUCCUCUACCCAAGAACCAUAGCCAUGAUUGUUAUAAAUCAAUGAAGUGUAAACAUACAUUAUUAAAAAACCACUUCUGACAUUCCAUUAUGUGCUAUUCAAAGAUGGACUAUUGAACUAUAGAAAAGACAGACUGUGCAUUUGUUCGUUGAUCCUCAUCUUAUUCCUGACAUGUAAAAAUCAAUUUUACGUAGAGUCAACAUUGUAGGUAGGUUAAAAUACCAGUGGCAAAUUUGGAAAUUCAGAAACUUAUAAACCACGAGAAAUAUAUAGGCUUGUCUCUUUGGUCUUUUAUUUUGGCUCUAUUGUUGGGAAUCUAUUUCCUAUUCUAUAAGUAAGUAUACCUAACAUGCUGUGGAAUCUUGAGUUUCCAACACCGUGCUGCUUGAUAGAAUGACUUUGAGGUCCUUGGAUAAAAUGUGAUAUAUGCAAGUACAGUAUGUUGCUAUUACUAUUGCAGGAAUAUAAAUAAUAAAAGACUGUUAUUAGCACUUAGUAAGUCUUCAUCUAUGCAUGUUUUUGAGUUGACUGAUUCCAAGAAUGAAAUAUGAGGUUUAUUGAAUUAUUCCUUUGAAAGGGAUCAAAACUUAUAUUCAAUGCACUUUAUAAUUAAUGGUGUCUAAAUGCCUCAGUCAGUGCCUAACUGCACAUACAAAAAUAAAACCUUCUUUCUGUAAUCUACCAAAAUAAACGCAAUGGUAUUUCUGCUAUUUAAACACAUCUUUAGCUUAUUUCUUCAUGUUCUGCUCUGGUUUUCAGUCAGUGUCUAUGUAAAGACACUUUUAGAGGAAAAUGUUGUAAUCCCAAAAGAAUUUUUGUUUAACCAACUUUCAGAGUUACUAAAAGGAUUAUCUUUAAUUCAGUAAAUAAUAGAAUAUAAUCUUCAAAAUUAGAAGAUAUUCUCUUAAAAUUUAUAACAAUUAAUGCAACAAAAAUCAGCAUAUUUUGAUAAAUGUCUCAAGCAAAUGAGCAACUCACAGGCCCCACAGGUGCCUACAGCCUGACCAGCUAUACAAAAAGCCUGCAACCUGAUUCUAGGAUAAAAUAUUAGAAAGCUCUCUGUUGCUAAAACAUCCAGAUAUAAACAUUUUGGUGGCUAAAAUCAAUGCCAUUUCCUCAUUGACAUUCUUUUAUUCAGCAAAUUUGUACAAAUAUACAUUUUCUCCUGUGCGAAUUUCAAAAAGCUAUAUUCAUUUUGAAGAGGAAAAUAAUAUGGCAUUAAAUGCUUUGUAUUUUCCCCUUAGUUAGCCCUUAUGGCAAAAAUAGUUGCUAAUCACUGAUACAAAGCAAAACGUUAUGGGUACUGAUAACAAAGUUCCAAAAGCCAAAAUGGGAUGAAUCACAAACUUACUGUUUUUCACUAAAACAUGUAAUUGGCCUAUUACAUCAAUAGUUUUAAGUGGGUAAUGUUCUUGAACAAUAUUAGAGCCAUAAAAUUGAAGCCAGUAGCUUGAACAAUAUGGAGGCCUUCUUACUGUAGGGAAGAGGUGUCUAGCUUAGAAGGAUCACAUUUGAUCUAGAUGAGAUUACCCAUAGCAGGGAAAAUGAAUCAUCACCUACCAAAGACUGUACGGAAAGGUGUGUUAUUUUCAAAAUUGCAUUUUAGUUUGCACACAUGUAAAUGAUUAUUCUAUGUUAAUCUAAUUGACAAUUCAGUUAGCUCCGCAUCCUAAGACUUAAAACUAGCAAUUCCUAUGCAAAUCAUCUGCUUAACUGAACUACAAACGUUUUUCAUUAAUUCAUUCUUUGAUGACAUAUUCCAUGUUAUAUAAUAAUUCAAAAUAAAGUUAAUAUACUACCCCA